CUCCCGGGGCGGCGGCGGUGGCGGCUCGGGCUGGGCUCCGCGUCGGGCCGGCCCCGCGGCCGCUCAUGGGCAGCCAGGGCCGCUCGGGGCCCCCCGGGAACGGCGGGCCCGGCGAGGGCGAGGGCGGAGAGGCGAGGAAGCUGCAGGAAGGGAGGGUGGCGAGGGGGAAGCGAAGGAAGGGGAAGGGGAAGGGAAAAGCGAGAGCGGGGCAAGGCGGAAGAGGAAGCGGGGCGGAAGGGAAGCCCGGGCCGCAGACGGCGAAGGAGGCAGCCGGGCCGGGGGCUGACGCGGGAGCGAGGGCAUGCCCAAGGGAGGAAGCAGAGGGAGGCAGAAGCGUGGAGGAAGGGGCGAGAGGCAUCGUCAAGGGAGUCGAGGGGAGCGCAGGGGCCGGGAAGGAGGCACAAGGAAGAGAGUAUGGGAAGAAGGAGGAAUGGAGGGUCAGGGCUAGGCGGCGGGAGGGCGCCAGGCCGGGAAGAGCACAGGGACGAGGGGGUCAGGCUUGGGCCGACAUCGCGGGGACAGGGGUGGCCAUGGCGGCGGCGGCCGGGGAGGAGGAGGAGGAGGAGGAGGCGGCUCGGGAGUCGGCUGCCCGCCCGGCCGCGGGGCCUGCGCUCUGGCGCCUGCCGGAGGAGCUGCUGCUGCUCAUCUGCUCCUACCUGGACAUGCGGGCCCUCGGCCGCCUGGCCCAGGUGUGCCGCUGGCUGCGGCGCUUCACCAGCUGCGAUCUGCUCUGGCGCCGGAUAGCCCGGGCCUCGCUCAACUCCGGCUUCACGCGGCUCGGCACCGACCUGAUGACCAGUGUCCCAGUGAAGGAACGAGUGAAGGUGUCUCAGAACUGGAGACUGGGGCGCUGCCGAGAGGGGAUUCUGCUGAAGUGGAGAUGCAGUCAGAUGCCCUGGAUGCAGCUAGAGGAUGAUUCUCUGUACAUAUCCCAGGCUAAUUUCAUCCUGGCCUACCAGUUCCGUCCAGAUGGUGCCAGCUUGAAUCGUCGGCCUCUGGGAGUCUUUGCUGGGCAUGAUGAGGACGUUUGCCACUUUGUGCUGGCCAACUCGCAUAUUGUUAGUGCAGGAGGGGAUGGGAAGAUUGGCAUUCAUAAGAUUCACAGCACCUUCACUGUCAAGUACUCGGCUCAUGAACAGGAGGUGAACUGUGUGGAUUGCAAAGGGGGCAUCAUUGUGAGUGGCUCCAGGGACAGGACGGCCAAGGUGUGGCCUUUGGCCUCAGGCCGGCUGGGGCAGUGCUUACACACCAUCCAGACUGAAGACCGAGUCUGGUCCAUUGCUAUCAGCCCAUUACUCAGCUCUUUUGUGACAGGGACGGCUUGUUGCGGGCACUUCUCACCCCUGAGAAUCUGGGACCUCAACAGUGGGCAGCUGAUGACACACUUGGGCAGUGACUUUCCCCCAGGGGCUGGGGUGCUGGAUGUCAUGUAUGAGUCCCCUUUCACACUGCUGUCCUGUGGCUAUGACACCUAUGUUCGCUACUGGGACCUCCGCACCAGCGUCCGGAAAUGUGUCAUGGAGUGGGAGGAGCCCCACGACAGCACCCUGUACUGCCUGCAGACAGAUGGCAACCACCUGCUGGCCACAGGUUCCUCCUACUACGGUGUUGUACGGCUGUGGGACCGGCGUCAAAGGGCCUGCCUGCACGCCUUCCCGCUGACGUCGACUCCCCUCAGCAGCCCUGUGUACUGCCUGCGUCUCACCACCAAGCAUCUCUAUGCUGCCCUGUCUUACAACCUCCACGUCCUGGAUUUUCAAAACCCAUGACCGUCAGGGCCACCCCUGCCUCUGGGCCAGGGAAACCAGCUACUCAGGGACUUCUCUUGCCUGGAGGGUGCAGUGAUAGCUCCUCCUCACUGCCCCACUGUGCUCCUGGGCCUGUGACCCCAGUGCUCAGGCACCUUGCACUAGAGGCUUCUGACUCCUGGGACUUUGGAGCUUACCAGAGAUGCAGUCCCUCCCAGGAACCUGUUGGAGAGGCAGGACCUGCUGCUUUAGAGUGCGGCUGAACCCGGGCCUUGCGUCCCUGUUUGGCCAGAGCAAGGAUCUGGCCUGGAGAGGCCCAUCCUAUACCCCUUAUUAGAGCCAUGACAGCCUACAGAGUGAGGUGAGGUGCUCCCACCUUCCCAGAUGGUUCCUUUCUGCCCCUUCCUGGAAGGAAAGGUGAGGCUGCCAAUAGCCUCCUGGCACCAGCCAGACCUCACCCUUGACCAACCUCUCGGGGCUGGGGGUUCAUUCCUGGGGCACUGUGGCCUGGUUUUGCUUUGAAACCAAGAAAGAGCAAAGGGAACCCAGCAGUUCUGAGUGAGUUCUGAGCCAGCCCUACCUCAGGCUGGCUGUUGAGACAUGCUACAAUUUUCAUUUUUGUAAAAAUAAAGCUUGAUUGUUCACA